AGUCGGGUCCAUCCUGCAGUAAAUGCACAACCCGGACGGAAGUGCCUCUCCGACAGCAGAUCCAGGCUCGGAGCUCCAGACGCUGGGACAGGCCGCCCGCAGACCACCCCCGCCGCGCGCGGGACACGACGCCCCCCGCAGGACCCGCCCAUCAGCCCGGAAACCCCUGAGCUGCUUCUCCCGGAGGCCGAUGCCCACCCGGGAGCCCCCAAAGACUCGCGGCUCCCGGGGGCACCUGCAUACUCACCCGCCUGGGCCUGGGCCCCCGCUGCAGGGACUGGCGCCCCGAGGCCUCAAAACCAGCGCCCCCCGCCCUCCGUGCCAGCCCCAGCCGGGACCCCACAAGGCAAAGACCAAGAAGAUUGUGUUUGAGGAUGAGUUGCUCUCCCAGGCCCUCCUGGGCGCCAAGAAGCCUAUUGGAGCCAUCCCUAAGGGGCAUAAGCCUAGGCCCCACCCAGUGCCCGACUAUGAGCUUAAGUACCCGCCAGUGAGCAGUGAGAGGGAACGGAGCCGCUAUGUCGCAGUGUUCCAGGACCAGUACGGAGAGUUCUUGGAGCUCCAGCACGAGGUGGGGUGUGCACAGGCAAAGCUCAGGCAGCUGGAGGCCCUGCUGAGCUCCCUGCCCCCACCCCAAAGCCAGAAGGAGGCCCAAGUUGCAGCCCGGGUUUGGAGGGAGUUUGAGAUGAAGCGAAUGGAUCCUGGCUUCCUGGACAAGCAGGCUCGCUGCCACUACCUGAAGGGUAAACUGAGGCAUCUCAAGACUCAGAUCCAGAAAUUCGAUGACCAAGGAGACAGCGAGGGCUCCGUGUACUUCUAAGUGCCCCUGCAGAUGGGCAGAGGGAUGCAUGGGGAUGCAGGUCCCUUGCAUUUCUUGGUAUCUCUCAGCUUUUCCUCUUGCAGCUCCCCCUACCAGGGGUCGCUUUCUCCUGGAUUGCAAAUGCCUCUUCAGUUUGGACUCAGCUCUGACAGCCCCUCCUCCAGGAAGGCCUUCCAGGACUUCCUCCUCUGGGUCCUCUAGCUCUGACCCUACAGGGACUCCAGAUCUCAACCUGUUCCCUGGAAGUAGGGCCUGCUCUCCAUCCCAGUGAAAUAAACAUGUAUUAGACACCUA